AGAGCUGUCAGCGGGCGGACGGGCAGCGGGUGACGGAGCGGCGAGACGAGCGCACAGCAGUCGCGGCCCGGGAGCCGGAGCUGCCGCCGCACCCCGGGAAGGCUGCCUUGCCGCCGGCCCGCCGACCGCGGCCGGACGAAGAUGCUGUUCCGCGCCCGGGGGCCGGUACGGGGCAGGGGCUGGGGGCGGCCGGCGGAGGCUCCCCGCCGCGGGCGCUCGCCGCCCUGGAGCCCCGCCUGGAUUUGCUGCUGGGCGCUCGCCGGCUGCCAGGCGGCCUGGGCUGGGGACCUGCCCUCCUCCUCCAGCCGCCCGCUUCCUCCUUGCCAGGAGAAAGAUUAUCACUUUGAAUAUACGGAAUGUGAUAGCAGUGGCUCCAGGUGGAGAGUUGCCAUUCCAAAUUCUGCAGUGGACUGCUCUGGCCUGCCUGACCCAGUGAGAGGCAAAGAAUGCACUUUCUCCUGUGCUUCUGGAGAGUAUCUAGAAAUGAAGAACCAGGUAUGCAGUAAGUGUGGUGAAGGCACCUAUUCCUUGGGCAGUGGCAUCAAAUUUGAUGAAUGGGAUGAAUUGCCGGCAGGAUUUUCUAACAUCGCAACAUUCAUGGACACUGUGGUGGGCCCUUCUGACAGCAGGCCAGACGGCUGUAACAACUCUUCUUGGAUCCCUCGUGGAAACUACAUAGAAUCUAAUCGUGAUGACUGCACGGUGUCUUUGAUCUAUGCUGUGCACCUUAAGAAGUCAGGCUAUGUCUUCUUUGAGUACCAGUAUGUCGACAACAACAUCUUCUUUGAGUUCUUUAUUCAAAAUGAUCAGUGCCAGGAGAUGGACACCACCACUGACAAGUGGGUAAAACUUACAGACAAUGGAGAAUGGGGCUCUCAUUCUGUAAUGCUGAAAUCAGGCACAAACAUACUCUACUGGAGAACUACAGGCAUCCUUAUGGGUUCUAAGGCGGUCAAGCCUGUGCUGGUAAAAAAUAUCACAAUUGAAGGGGUGGCGUACACAUCAGAAUGUUUUCCUUGCAAGCCAGGCACAUUCAGCAACAAACCAGGUUCAUUCAACUGCCAGGUGUGUCCCAGAAACACCUAUUCUGAGAAAGGAGCCAAAGAAUGUAUAAGGUGUAAAGACGACUCUCAAUUUUCAGAGGAAGGAUCCAGUGAGUGUACAGAGCGCCCUCCCUGUACCACAAAAGACUAUUUCCAGAUCCAUACUCCAUGUGAUGAAGAAGGAAAGACACAGAUAAUGUACAAGUGGAUAGAGCCCAAAAUCUGCCGGGAGGAUCUCACAGAUGCUAUUAGAUUGCCCCCUUCUGGAGAGAAGAAGGAUUGUCCGCCUUGCAACCCUGGAUUUUAUAACAAUGGAUCAUCUUCUUGCCAUCCCUGUCCUCCUGGAACAUUUUCAGAUGGAACCAAAGAAUGUAGACCAUGUCCAGCAGGAACGGAGCCUGCACUUGGCUUUGAAUAUAAAUGGUGGAAUGUCCUUCCUGGCAACAUGAAAACUUCCUGCUUCAAUGUUGGGAAUUCAAAGUGCGAUGGAAUGAAUGGUUGGGAGGUGGCUGGAGAUCAUAUCCAGAGUGGGGCUGGAGGUUCUGACAAUGAUUACCUGAUCUUAAACUUGCAUAUCCCAGGAUUUAAACCACCAACAUCUAUGACUGGAGCCACGGGUUCUGAACUAGGAAGAAUAACAUUUGUCUUUGAGACCCUCUGUUCAGCUGACUGUGUUUUGUACUUCAUGGUGGAUAUUAAUAGAAAAAGUACAAAUGUGGUAGAAUCGUGGGGUGGAACCAAAGAAAAACAAGCUUACACCCAUAUCAUCUUCAAGAAUGCAACUUUUACAUUUACAUGGGCAUUCCAGAGAACUAAUCAGGGUCAAGAUAAUAGACGGUUCAUCAAUGACAUGGUGAAGAUUUAUUCUAUCACAGCCACUAAUGCAGUUGAUGGGGUGGCGUCCUCAUGCCGUGCCUGUGCCCUCGGUUCUGAACAGUCGGGUUCAUCGUGUGUCCCCUGCCCUCCAGGCCACUACAUUGAGAAAGAAACCAACCAGUGCAAGGAAUGUCCACCUGACACCUACCUGUCCAUACAUCAGGUCUAUGGCAAAGAGGCUUGUAUUCCAUGCGGGCCUGGGAGUAAAAACAAUCAGGACCAUUCGGUUUGCUAUAGUGACUGCUUUUUCUACCAUGAAAAAGAAAAUCAGAGUUUGCACUAUGACUUUAGCAACCUCAGCAGUGUGGGCUCAUUAAUGAAUGGCCCCAGCUUCACCUCCAAAGGAACAAAAUACUUCCAUUUCUUCAAUAUCAGUUUAUGUGGGCAUGAGGGGAAGAAGAUGGCUCUCUGUACCAACAAUAUAACAGACUUUACAGUAAAAGAAAUAGUGGCAGGGUCAGAUGAUUACACAAAUUUGGUAGGGGCAUUUGUAUGCCAGUCAACAAUUAUUCCUUCUGAAAGUAAGGGUUUCCGAGCAGCCUUAUCAUCACAAUCCAUCAUUCUGGCAGAUACAUUCAUAGGAGUCACAGUUGAAACCACAUUGAAAAAUAUUAAUAUAAAAGAAGAUAUGUUCCCAGUUCCAACAAGCCAAAUACCAGAUGUGCAUUUCUUUUAUAAGUCUUCUACAGCAACAACAUCUUGUAUUAAUGGCCGAUCAACUGCUGUGAAAAUGAGGUGUAAUCCUACUAAAUCUGGAGCAGGAGUGAUUUCAGUCCCCAGCAAGUGCCCAGCAGGUACCUGUGAUGGGUGUACGUUCUAUUUCCUGUGGGAGAGUGCUGAAGCUUGCCCUCUGUGUACGGAGCAUGACUUCCAUGAGAUUGAGGGAGCCUGCAAGAGAGGAUUUCAGGAAACCUUGUAUGUGUGGAAUGAACCUAAAUGGUGCAUUAAAGGAAUUUCUUUGCCUGAGAAAAAGUUGGCAACCUGUGAAACGGUUGACUUUUGGCUGAAGGUGGGAGCCGGUGUGGGAGCUUUUACUGCCGUUUUGCUGGUGGCUCUGACCUGCUACUUCUGGAAAAAGAAUCAAAAACUGGAAUACAAAUAUUCCAAGUUAGUAAUGACGACUAACUCAAAAGAGUGUGAACUCCCGGCUGCAGACAGUUGUGCUAUCAUGGAAGGAGAAGAUAAUGAAGAGGAAGUUGUAUAUUCCAAUAAACAGUCACUACUAGGAAAACUCAAAUCUUUGGCAACCAAGGUGAGAGUAGAAUUUUAACCUGGUGUUACUGGGUGUUUAUAAAGUAGAGGGCAUAUUAACCUAAUAAUAGCAUUCACGCAAGCUGUUAUUUUGCAUGUUUAUAUCUCAGUGGGUAUUUAUCCAACAGAAAUACUCUUAGAAGCACAUGAUAUAGAUACAAUAAUAUUCACUGCAGCAUUGUUUUCGUUGGUUGUCAAACAUCAUCAGUAAGGAGUUAGAUAUUUUCAUCUGUCAAAGUGAUAGAAUACUAUGCAACUCUGCAGCUGUUAAAGAUUGAGAUAGCUAUGUGUACUGAUAAAUCAAUAGGUCCAAGAUAGAGUGAAAACAAAUGGACUAUUGUAUUUAUAUUAAAUAUACAUUUAUGUUUGUAUUUGCAUAGCAAACUGUUAACAGUGGCUGCCUUUUGGGAAUAGUGAACUAAUGAGAGUGUUUAGUCUUUGAAAGCAAUACAUUUUUGUGAUAUUGGAAUUUUCACAAAGAUACUAUUUUAUAAUAUAAAAGUGGGGGCUAAUAAAAGAUAUUACAUUCAUUCAUACUGUUCCUUUUUUAUGACAAGAUUGUUUUACAUAGAGCAAACAAAAGUUAUAUAAAUUAUUGAGGUAUGUGAGGUAAAAUAUUGCUGGCUUUGGAUUUUGGAACAACUACCAUAUCCAAACAUAACAUGAAACCAUACAUUGUUUGAAAAGACAUUUUAUUUGAUAUUUUUCACCAUUGACUUAAAAGAUGAGAAAUUAUCAGCUUACUUAAGAUUAAAAAAGAAUGAAAUAGAAGAAAGAAGAUGACUUUCAAAUGAUUUAUAACAGGAUAGACAAGAGACAAAAUUUACAUUUAUAAAGAGUAAUAGUAACCAUUUCCUUGUACUCUCCUAAUUUAGGCACAUAAAUAUAGGGAAUUAUUUAAGAGUAAAAAUGAAUAAACCGUCUUUCCCUUCUACUAAUGGUUAAUUUUUCCUUUUAUUAAUAUGAAGAUGUAAGGAGGGUACUAUUGCCAUAAAAUAACAAAAAAAUAGUGAUUAUUAAGAUCGGAGAUCUUUACCCUACUUGCAAGCUAACAAGUGAGUCUGCUACAGUUUCAUGGACAGUUUAGAAGACAUGAGAGUCAUGUCAGAGAUGAAGGACAGUUUCGUAUUCAUAGAGUAGUGCUAGCAGAGUAAUAACCUUUAUACCAGCUCCCAAAGCCACAGGUAGCCCACAAGGCUGUGUUCCCACAGCGCUAUUUGCAGAGGAAAUGAUAUCACUUGGUUGCAUUACAGGAAAGGGAUGCUAGGCCUUAGGAACCUGAAUGUUCAUAAUGAACAGUAAACAUGCCCAUCCUUUGCCUCAAAGGGGGCUAUUAUCUUUAUUGUUUUGGACAGGUAGCAUACCUGUCCAUUGCUUCUGGGAGACACUAUUUCCAAGACUGUAAGCAAGCCUACCCUUUGCUCAGGAAGGAGACAAUAUAUCUUUAUAUUCCAAGGAAAUUUUCUAUACAAAGAUUCUUGAAAAGAUAGUCUAGAACAAAGGGUAAUCAGUUUCUCACUUUUAAGAUGUACAGAAAUGAAAGAGAACCAUGGAGAAUUGUCUCCAACAACAUCCAAACCUCAUUUUUAUACCAUGUUGGUUUCUGAUGAAUUUUCCCUUUAUUUCCCCACUCCAUGCACCAUUCUGAUUAAUAUGACUGACUGAAGCUGGGAUCAAAUUUGAUCAAUUUGCUUUAUACAGCAUUUAAAUAAAGCUACUACCAAUAGGACACCAAGCAGAAGUCAUCUCACCAAGAUGAGGCCAAUCUGUAUUGUUAACCUCAACCCUACCCUCAGGGUCCCAGACUCAACUAGCUGAACAAAUGCUAUGAACCAUCAGGGUUUACCUUAGAAAGCUAGAUAGCUUUCUUGUGUUGACCUUUCCACUGGCACUCAGAUAUUUCCUCCAUAAGAUUUGGACAAAAAGGGGACAAGGAAAUUUUCAAAAUCUUAACAGAAACCCAAUAUACAGAAGUCCUCCCUUAUUUGCAGUUUCACUUUUCAUGGUCUUACUUUUUGUGGUUUUAGUUACCCACCGUCAACUGUGGUCUGCAAACAUUACAUGGAAAAUUCCAGAAGUAAACAACAAGUUUUAAAUUGUGUGCUCCUCUGAAUAGUGUGACGAAAUCUCCUACUGUACUGCCUUGUCCCCCCCGGAAGUAAAUCAUCCCUUUAUCUAGCAUAUCUUUGCCAUAUACACUACCUGCUUGUUAGUUACUUAGUAGUCAUUUUGAUUAUCAGAUUGAAAAAAAAAACAAAACCAGUAUUAUAGGGUUUGAUACUAUACUUGGUUUCAGGCAUCCACUGGAGCUGGGGGGGAGUUGGAAUGUAUCCCCUGGGAAUAGGGUGGGGGGUACUGUAUCUCUGAUUUUUGUCACACACUUGGUGAGCAGUAAACUCAAUCAAGUGGUUACUAUCCUUUUGAUCUAGGGUCAUGGCAAUCCAACAAGACAAUCCAGAUACAUUAAUCCAGGUACUACAGGAUAUAUUAGUGAUUGCACAGACUUUGUCUUGGUUCUCAAAGAGAAAGUAUAGGGUAAUUAUAUUGUGAAUAACAAUGUAUGGACAGUGAGUUGAUGUUGACCUGAAUGCCUUUGAUGGCUGAGGUGGUGUAAUUGAUUACUUCAAGCUAAGGUCAAAGGCAAAUUUUAUACCACCUUUUCUAACAUCCAUAACAGUAGGGGUAUUUUCCUAAACAGUUGAAGAUCUCUUAUGACUACUCCUAAGGUGUAAGUUAUCAUGUUUUUAGUGAGGAAGCAAGUUAGUGUCUGACUUCUACACAAGAAGUGCAGUCCUGGAGGUACACAUGGUGCCUCUGCAAAGAAAGUGUUAUUCACAGUUGUGGGGUACAUGAAGUGGGACCUACAUUGUGCAGGCAGCACAGGUUGACUGUUCCUGUAAGUGGCUUCUUUGCUGGCUAGUAAGCCUUAGGGUUUCCAAUUCACCUCAUAUAAUGAUGUCUCCUUUUUGUCUUCAGGGAGACUGCUUGAGGGAAGUCAGCUCAACUCUCCCUGUUUGUCCACACUGCAAACUAGUGACUUUUGUUCACCUCAUGAAAUGACUAAAUAAUGGCUAUGGAAAUGAGAUGUUGGUGUUACUCUGGGGCAGGGGCUGAGGCCAUUUCCUGCUCUUUUGGAUAAAUUUCUCAGUUAGUUUAAGGGGAAUGGCAAAUGAAUUGUGAUGAGAGCAUGUGGUGGGUAUGGCAGACCCAGCAGUUAGUUAAAUUAAAGGCCUUUGCCAUGAUUUGAGAGAGCCACAUCAGAGCAUUUUUCUUCAUAGGAAGGUGACAGGGUGACCCUAAAAAAUCAUAUGAUUCUUAAUGUCCCUUAUUUCCCCAUACUUCUCAGGGUCUAAGCUGUCUCCUCCAUUAUCAGACUGUGUUGUUGUCUCUUUCCAGUGCUAAAAAACCAGCUUGUCUCAUUUCAGUAACUAUAAUUUCACCUUAUUUCUACCCAUAUCUAUCCAGAACAUUCAUGUGCAAGAGGGAUAAAGGCAUUUUAUAGAAACAUAUAGAGACUCAGUGUGUACCCCCGCUUUGUCCAUGUGGGCCAUGAUAGGGGGACUUGGGGGGCAGUGCACUCAUCAGGUGGUCAUUAUCUCUCUUAUCUAUAAUCAUGACAGCCAACAAAGCAACAAUACAGGUGGUUAAACCAGAAUUAUAUUUGAAUUUCCUAGAUCCCCUUCUGGGUGGGCUAUCACUAGAAGUUGUACCCAGGAAGCCUGAGGUUACUGUUGGAGUAAAUAACACAUCAUGCCCUAGAUUGGUGAGGCAGAAUCCAGGAUGUUCAGAUAAGUGUAAAUAACCUUAUGUAGUGGUGUAUAUGUGUGUCUGUCUGUGUGUAUGUAUGUGUAUGUGUGUUCUUCCUGAUCAUUAUCUGUGAAGUGGCCAAAAGGAGAUGAUCCCUUUCCAUGGGCAGCCAUAUUUGAUGACCAAACUGCUGUAUUAAGAUGUGUGGAUCAGGAGGAGGUGAGGGAGAUAGAGUCAGAAAUCUUUUUGAGUCACUUUCUGAGAAGGUCUUACAAUGCUCAAUAGUACCAUAUGCUUUUGGACAGUAGGAAAUGUAGAAGGUCCGCUGAAUACCUCUACUCUCAACUAAUUUAUGGGUAGCUUUUGUGAUAAAAAGUGUCCUAUUGUCAGACAGCAAAUGGUCUUUAAAGCUACCAACUUUAUACUGAUUUGUUUCAAGGUUCACAAUGUAUGGGUAGAGUUAGCUGAUCAGACUGGAAUAGCAACACCAUACCCUGAACAGUUGUAAAUAGUGGUGAGGCAUCACCAGUAGCCCAAAGAGGUGGUCAAAGGUAUUUUGUAAUCAAUUUGCCCAGGAAGAACUGGUCAACUUUUGGCAUGAGUCCCAAGUCUGGCAUCUGCAGUAACCUCUGCAUAAGAAAAAUAUGUGCCCUUGUGCCCAGUCUAUGAUGGCAGAUGCUUUGCCAUGUUGGGGGAGAUGAUGGACCCAUGCACCAUUUGUGACAGUCUGUCUUGUCUAGUCUCUAUCAGGAGCUUGAUUCAAUUUCAUCUUUCAUAAGAAGGAUCCUUACCUGGGCAUCUACAUGAGUGACACAUAUUUUAAUCCAAAACUAAGAUCUAUUUUAGUGGUAUCCAAAAAGGGUAACCUUGAAAUGCCAGUCUUUAAUUUUCCAAGUGGCAGACAAAACAGCCAGCCAUUGGCAAUAGCUUGAGUCAGUAAGUCAGAAAAAUAUAAUGAAGUUUAUCAAGGGAGGUAAUGUGUAGGUCUUGAUAAUGCCUUUGAGUUCUGUCCACUGAGCUGAGCAAUCUUGUUGGUUUUCAGUUAUUCAUAGAUGAUUGAAUAUCUGUAGCAGCCAGUGGAUACCACUGGGCUUCAGCUCAACCAAAUCAUCAGUGAACCAGGCCCAACAUGUAGUAGAACCUCGAUAAAUCGAGGGUCCUAUUGAGUCAGUGGUUUUGUUUUGAGCCGUGGAGUAGGGGAUAAAGUUUCCCCCAAAGGGUAUGCUGCCACAUUUUUAUGUGAGGCCUACAUGCCACUGGGGCAAGACCAACUGCAUUCUUGAAUAUAUGCCAUUCGUAUUUGACAAGUGAGGCUUAUUCAGCCUUUUCUACCUUGUUGAGCGACCAUAAAUGGGACUAUCAAGCUGUAGAGUCACAAGAUCUGGGGCAUGGGAAUGAAAUUUAGUUUUGACUAGUUCAGUGACCAACUAAUGGCUAUAGCUGGUAGCCAUAUCAAGAGGUAAUGAGUCUAAAACCUCAAAGGGUACCUCUGUCUCCUCUUGCCAGAGUCUCCAAUUGGCAAAAUCAUUAGUUAUAGAGAAUUGUAUCACAAAGUUGUCAUUAUGAUUGUGAGGCCAUAAAGGUAAAGAGUGUGCCCCAGCUUUCUGGACAGCUUUUAACAUAGCCUGUUAGUUUGGGUCCAAUUCAAAGGAUACUAUUUUGUAGGCUAGCUGAUAUAAAAGAACAAGUAGAAUACUCAAAUGCGGUCCAACACUGUCCCAAUAGCAGAGUCAAGUAAAGUGCUGGGCUGUUUUUCCUUAACUGCUGGGUAGAUUUAGCACUGUAAAUCUGCUUACAUAGUUCCAAUGAACUUUACUUAGGUAGCAGGUCCCUGAAUGUUUUGGGGGUUUAUCAACCACCUCUGUAAGUAGAAGUGUCAUAACUCAAUCAGGGCUGUUGAUAUGGAGACUUCUGACUUGACACCAAAAGGACCUAAUUUAUAUAGUGACUGUUUUGGGCAUCAGAAGGUAAAGGAACUUGUGUGAAACCCUGACUCACCAUUUGUUGCAAAUGGCAGUUGGAAACUCCUGGGGUAUCCUACUGCCUACUGGCCCUUCUCUACAUGUAGCUGUUCUUGGUUAAGGGAUCUCCUUUAGCAUGUAUGAGAUGGGGAAGUACAAGCAUAUAACAUCAAGUUCUACUGUAUAUUCAGAUGUAGAAGCAACAACAACACUAUCUUGAAUGGACACAUAGAAUCCCUCCAAAGAUCACAUUAUUUUCCCUUUUCUACUCUAAACCUUGCUCAAAUCCUCUUAUUUGUAUGCUCCUCUUUUCCCACAGGAGAGUAGGUAUGAUGGUGACUUGAGUGCCUGCAACCAACAGAGUGGUAAAUGUUUAAGAAACCCUCUCCAGGUUUUCCUAGCAGAUUCAGAUGGGUGUGUAUUGUCCAGUCCCUCUUGGUAACAGGAAAACUUUAGUCCCCUUUCUAAUUAUCUUUUUUCUUGAAGCAGCUGAAGUUGGGGUAGUUUGGGAGGGAGGCAUUAAGACUGAAGAGAGAGAGAAUCUUUGACAGUAGACAAGAUGUUUGCAUUCACUUUUAUUUUUGACCAGCAUAUCAGCUGCUAAUGAUCCAACCAACUUCCAAUGCUUUCAAUGUUUUUGGUCUACCCAAAGGCCUAUGUUGAACAGCAAGGUUCUGUUUACUGACAUCAUUUAUUUGAGCUUUGGGGACCCCUUAACUUAGAGGCCACUUUCAUAUUGCUUUUUCUCUGAGGCUGCAGGUUUUAUGUCCUUUUGUUGAUUUGUACUUGACUUGCAUAUUGGAGACAUGUUUAAAGAAUCUAUCUUAAUCCAGAGUAUUUCUUGCUAUUGUUAAUAAUGUUUAAUGUAAUUCCUGGUUUUAACAUAAAAGUAGGGGAAAUUUCCAGGUAGACCUGACCAUACUAAUUUAUCUAGAGUCCUUUGGAUCAGUUUCUCAUUCUCUAGUGAACUUCUUCCGCGUUGUAAACCCAAUCUGCGACAAUAAGAGUCCAAAUAUGAGUCAAUGCUUCACUAAGUUUUCCUAUGGGAAUCAGUCUCAGGGAAAGCUCUCUGUAUUGUAGUCAGGACCCACUUCAAAAUCUCUGGGACCUUUUUACUGUCAUCUAUGAAUAUAUCUAAAAUUUGCAUGAUAGAUUGCAAGAGGUGUUGAGCCCAAAAAUGGCCCACCUGCUUGUCAUUCUGAAUUGCUUACCAAACAGUCAUUGAGUCCUGCCAAAUUAUCUCUAAAGUGAGUCAGUCAAAAUUUUCGUAAUCUCUCAGGUUUCUUCCCAUAAAUGAUUUCCAUUUUUCCCUUUUAGUACUCCUUGUAGAUGAUGCAUGUCUCUGUAAUUUUUAUCUAAAAGAGGGUGAAACCUCCUUUGCCUACCAGGAUGAAUUUUAGCUGUACGGUCAUACAGGAUUGGUUCCAGGGCCCCUGAGUAUACCAAAAUUCAAGCAUACUUAAAUCCUGCAGUCAGCUCUGCAGAGCCAGCCUAUGUGAAAAGUCAGCUCUCUAUUUAGGUGGCUUUCACCUCCCACCAAUGCUGUAUUUUCAAUCCGGGUUCAGUUUUGUAAAAUCUGCCUAUAAGUAGGCCUGUGCAGUUCAAACUUGUGGUGUUCAAAGGUCAACUGUAGUUCUUACCAUGGGGCAUACCUAAGGCUGAUUGCCUGGUGAAUGAGGAAGUCUUUCGGGCUAGAGGAUAAUUAAAGCAUCCAGGGCACUGUUGAGGCAGGUGAACUGUGAAUUCUUUAACCCAUUUCCCAGUCAGUACUCAACAAGCAGUCACCUCUCCAAUUAGAGUAUAAAAAAGUUUUCUUCCCUGAGAAGAUUCAGGGUAGUGAAUUUUGUUUUGAAUAGCAAUUUUAGUUAGCGUAAUGAUUUUUUUACUUUAAAAAUGAAAUUUUGAAAUAGUACAGAAAAGUUGAAAGAAUCAUACAGUGGUAUAGUCAUAUGCCCACCAUACAAAUUUUAUUAUAUUUGUAUUAUUACAUAUCCGUCCCUCCAUCCUUUCAUCAACCCAUAUUCUUUUCUGUUGUUCGGUUUCAAAGUAAAUUGCAGACUUCAAUACACUUCACCCCAAAACACUUCAGGGAACUUAUCAUUGAUGAUAAUUCAAUACUUAAGUUUGUUUUAAGUGAAAGGCACACAUUACAAAUAUACAAUUUAAUGAAUUUUGAGAAAUGAAUAUACAUCUAUAACCCCCAAUUCCUAUCAAGAUAUAGAACACUAGUUCACCCCUGAGAGUAACAUGUAUUUUUACAUGCAGUCAAUCCCACAUCUCCCAAAGGAAACUACUGUAAUGAUCUUUUUAAACCAUAGGUUAGUGUUAUCUGUUAUAGAACUUCAUAUAAAUGUAAUCACACAGUAUCUGUAGUAUUUUGUGUACAUUUUACUUUACUCAGAAAGAUAUUUUUGAGAUUCAUUCGCCUCGUGUUAACAGAAGUAGAUUCCUUUGUAUUCCAGAGUAGUAUUCUAUUGUGUAGAUAUACCAACAUUUGUUUAUCCAGUCUGUUGAUUGAUACCUGUGCUAUUUCCAGUGUUUGACAAUGAAUAAAGCUACUAUAAAUAUCGUUGCACAUAUCUUAUUGUGUGUCUAUUUUUAAGAAGUUUGUUAUACAUGAUUUCAGAGAGCAAAAAAUGUUUAUGUUCAUUAACUAUUAUGUCAUAUAGGGUUUGCUUUAUCUUAGAUAUGCUCAUUUAUGUUCUAAAGGCCAUACCUUAUUUGAUAUUUCCCUAGCACUGCACUGCAAUUCUCGGGUUUAUGUAUAGAUUUAUUAUUCUUGACUUUUCUCAGCAAUUAAAACUAAAUCAAUUUUUA